AGCGUCUUGGCGGCAGUUGGUGGAACCGGAGCUUCGAGUCCGUCCCCGGUGCUGCCUGCGCGUUCACCUGAGUCUCGCUGGAGCUCUUCUCGCCCGCCCACCUCAUCUCAACCCACUUUCCGCGGGGAGCGGCGCCAAGCUGGGCCUUCCUCGGAUCAGGCGUCCCCUGAAGUCGGCACGCCCCUCUGCGUCCCCCUUCGGUCCCGCUAGGACCCCGUCCGGGCUGCCGUCGCCUCGUCGCUAUGGCGCCCACCAUCCAGACCCAGGCCCAGCGGGAGGAUGGCCACAGGCCCAAUUCCCACCGGACUCUGCCUGAGAGGUCUGGAGUGGUCUGCCGAGUCAAGUACUGCAAUAGCCUCCCUGAUAUCCCCUUCGACCCCAAGUUCAUCACCUACCCCUUCGACCAGAACAGGUUCGUCCAGUACAAAGCCACUUCCUUGGAGAAACAGCACAAACAUGACCUCCUGACUGAGCCAGACCUGGGGGUCACCAUCGAUCUCAUCAAUCCUGACACCUACCGCAUCGACCCCAAUGUUCUUCUAGAUCCAGCUGAUGAGAAACUUUUGGAAGAGGAGAUUCAGGCCCCCACCAGCUCCAAGAGAUCCCAGCAGCACGCGAAGGUGGUGCCAUGGAUGCGAAAGACAGAGUACAUCUCCACUGAGUUCAACCGUUAUGGCAUCUCCAAUGAGAAGCCUGAGGUCAAGAUUGGGGUUUCUGUGAAGCAGCAGUUUACCGAGGAAGAAAUAUACAAAGACAGGGAUAGCCAGAUCACAGCCAUUGAGAAGACUUUUGAGGAUGCCCAGAAAUCAAUCUCACAGCAUUACAGCAAACCCCGAGUCACACCGGUGGAGGUCAUGCCUGUCUUCCCAGACUUUAAGAUGUGGAUCAAUCCAUGUGCUCAGGUGAUCUUUGACUCAGACCCAGCCCCCAAGGACACGAGUGGUGCAGCUGCGUUGGAGAUGAUGUCUCAGGCCAUGAUUAGGGGCAUGAUGGAUGAGGAAGGGAACCAGUUUGUGGCCUAUUUCCUGCCUGUAGAAGAGACGUUGAAGAAACGAAAGCGGGACCAGGAGGAGGAGAUGGACUAUGCACCAGAUGAUGUGUAUGACUACAAAAUUGCUCGGGAGUACAACUGGAACGUGAAGAACAAAGCUAGCAAGGGCUAUGAGGAAAACUACUUCUUCAUCUUCCGAGAGGGUGACGGGGUUUACUACAAUGAGUUGGAAACCAGGGUCCGCCUUAGUAAGCGCCGGGCCAAGGCUGGGGUUCAGUCAGGCACCAACGCCCUGCUUGUGGUCAAACAUCGGGACAUGAAUGAGAAGGAACUGGAAGCUCAGGAGGCACGGAAGGCCCAGCUAGAAAACCACGAACCGGAGGAGGAAGAGGAAGAGGAGAUGGAGACAGAAGAGAAAGAAGCUGGGGGCUCAGAUGAGGAGCAGGAGAAGGGCAGCAGCAGUGAGAAGGAGGGCAGUGAAGAUGAGCACUCGGGCAGCGAGAGUGAACGGGAGGAAGGUGACAGGGACGAGGCCAGUGACAAGAGUGGCAGUGGUGAGGACGAGAGCAGCGAGGAUGAGGCCCGGGCUGCCCGUGACAAAGAGGAGAUCUUUGGCAGUGAUGCUGAUUCUGAGGACGAUGCCGACUCUGAUGAUGAGGACAGAGGACAGGCCCAAGGUGGCAGUGACAAUGAUUCAGACAGCGGCAGCAAUGGGGGUGGCCAGCGGAGCCGGAGCCACAGCCGCAGCGCCAGUCCCUUCCCCAGUGGCAGCGAGCACUCGGCCCAGGAGGAUGGCAGUGAAGCUGCAGCUUCUGAUUCCAGUGAAGCUGAUAGUGACAGUGACUGAGUCCCAGGGCAUUCAGGGCUGGUUCAGACACCAUUAUUGUGAGCAGCAAAGCACUUUUCUAGUGGUCUGUUUGUGAGCCUUUCACUUGUUUGUUCCCCACCCCCAAACCUUUGCUGUUAAUAAAGUCAACUUCUCUUUACUUCCCCUCCCAGCCCCUAUGAUGUCAUUCAGCCCAGCACAUACCUCCCGCAACCCCCAGGUGCUCAAGGAUCUUGGCUUGAGGCUUAGAAACACAGGCCAGAGGCAGGGCCAAUGGUUUCCCACAAAAUGUAGCACAACGAAGGUCAGAAUUCGUUUUUUUUGUUUGUUUUUUUUUUUUCCAAAAUAAGCCCAGACCAUUAAACAAGUGAAACUCCAACAAA